AAUGAAACCUUCAAAAAGCAUGAGUACGUAAUGAAUGGCUACCUGUGUUAUUGACAUUGCUGUGCUACUGUAUGUAUUUCGGUUUUAGAAGGCGUAACACAUUUAAAGGAUAUCCACAAUUUCCUUCAAAAUAUAGAGGACAUGCAGUGAGGACAUGGAAGAGGAAAAUGCAACAUUGCUGACAGAGUUUGUUCUCACAGGAUUUUUAUAUCAACCACAGUGGAAAAUACCCCUGUUCUUGGCAUUCUUGGUAAUAUAUCUCAUCACCAUCAUGGGGAAUCUUGGUCUGAUUGCUGUCAUCUGGAAAGACCCUCACCUUCAUAUCCCAAUGUACUUACUCCUUGGGAAUUUAGCUUUUGUGGAUGCUUGGAUAUCAUCCACAGUGACCCCAAAGAUGCUGAAUAACUUCUUAGCUAAGAGUAAGAUGAUAUCUCUCUCUGAAUGCAAGAUACAAUUUUUUUCCAUUGCAAUUGGCGUAACCACAGAAUGUUUUCUCUUGGCAACAAUGGCAUAUGAUCGCUAUGUAGCCAUAUGCAAACCUUUACUUUAUCCAGCCAUUAUGACCAAUGGACUGUGCAUCCGGCUAUUAAUCUUGUCAUAUAUAGCUGGUAUUCUUCAUGCUUUAAUCCAUGAAGGAUUUUUAUUCAGACUAACCUUCUGUAACUCCAACAUAGUACAUCACAUUUACUGUGACACUAUCCCAUUGUCUAAGAUUUCUUGUACUGAUUCUUCUAUUAAUUUUCUAAUGGUUUUUAUUUUCUCAGGUUCAAUUCAGGUAUUCAGCAUUGUGACUAUUCUUAUAUCUUACACAUUUGUUCUCUUCACAGUCUUAGAAAAGAAAUCUGAUAAGGGUGUAAGGAAAGCCUUUUCCACCUGUGGAGCCCAUCUCUUCUCUGUCUGUUUAUACUAUGGCCCCCUUCUCUUAAUGUAUGUGGGCCCUGCAUCUCCGCAAGCAGAUGGUCAAAAUAUGGUGGAGCCUCUAUUCUACACUGUCAUCAUUCCUUUGUUAAAUCCUAUCAUCUACAGUCUGAGAAAUAAGCAAGUCAUAGUUUCAUUCAUAAAAAUGUUAAAAAGAAAUGUUAAGGUUUCAUACUAAUAUCCUUUUUCUAUUUACUAAAAUAGUCACAAAAUUACGCAAGUUAGAGGUACCUAUGUUGUUUCCAGUGUUCAAACAUUUUUGCAAGUAUAACUGUCCUAGCACUUUAAUGACCUAACAUUUUAGUACCUAA